GACCCGGAAGCCGCCGUGGCCGCCGCACAAGCUGCGCUCGUCUCUCGGCUGGGGAGCUCCGUGUCGCACCGGGUUCUUGGGCUGGCCGUGUCCUUCUCCCUCGGUCGCCACUGGCCCAUGAGUCCCCAUGGCGACGGCAGGGGCCAGGCCCAGGGGCGGGCAGUCCGAGUGGGGCUGCGGCGCUCCGGGGGCAUCCGCGGCGGCGUGGCGGUGUUCGCCGCCGUGGCCGCAGUGUUCACCUUCACCCUGCCCCCUUCGGUACCGGGGGGAGACUCCGGGGAACUGAUCACAGCCGCACAUGAGCUUGGAGUUGCCCAUCCUCCUGGCUAUCCUUUGUUCACGCUGGUGGCUAAACUGGCAAUUACACUGUUUCCUUUUGGUUCAAUUGCCUACCGCGUCAAUCUUCUCUGUGGCUUAUUUGGAGCAGUAGCUGCAUCAUUACUUUUUUUCACCGUUUUCAGGCUUUCUGGCUCAUCUGCUGGAGGAAUCCUUGCUGCGGGGGUGUUUUCAUUUUCUCGUCUAACAUGGCAGUGGUCCAUUGCAGCAGAGGUUUUUAGCUUAAACAAUCUCUUUGUGGGGCUGCUUAUGGCUCUUACUGUACAUUUUGAGGAAGCAGCAACUGCUAAGGAGAGAUCAAAGGUAGCUAAAAUUGGUGCUUUCUGCUGUGGCCUUAGUUUAUGUAACCAGCACACAAUAAUACUCUAUGUUUUGUGCAUAAUACCUUGGAUUCUCUUUCAACUUUUAAAAAAGAAGGAACUCUCCCUGGGCUCUUUGUUGAAGUUGAGCCUGUACUUCUCUGCUGGUUUGCUGCCCUAUGUCCACCUUCCCAUCUCAUCUUACCUUAAUCACGCCCGGUGGACCUGGGGAGACCAGACAACACUGCAAGGAUUUUUGACACAUUUUCUCAGGGAAGAAUAUGGAACCUUCAGCCUGGCCAAAUCUGAAAUAGGAUCCAGUAUGUCUGAAAUACUGCUUUCUCAAGUAACAAAUAUGAGGACCGAACUCUCAUUCAACAUCCAAGCCCUUGCAGUUUGUGCAAAUAUAUGUUUAGCAACAAAGGACAGACAGAAUCCAUCAUUAGUAUGGCUUUUUACUGGAAUGUUUUGCAUUUAUUCAUUGUUCUUUGCUUGGAGAGCAAAUUUAGAUAUUUCAAAACCACUUUUCAUGGGUGUGGUGGAACGAUUCUGGAUGCAGAGCAAUGCAGUAGUGGCCGUCCUCGCUGGCAUUGGUUUGGCUGCAGUUGUGUCUGAGACUAACCGAGUGCUGAAUAGCAAUGGGCUUCAGUGUCUGGAAUGGCUUUCUGCAACUCUUUUUGUAGUUUACCAAAUAUAUUCUAAUUACAGUGUUUGUGACCAAAGGACCAACUAUGUGAUUGAUAAGUUCGCAAAGAACCUUCUCACCUCUAUGCCUCAUGAUGCAAUUAUCUUACUCAGAGGAGAUUUGCCAGGAAAUUCUCUCCGUUACAUGCAUUACUGUGAGGGGUUGAGGCCUGACAUUUCAUUAGUGGAUCAGGAAAUGAUGACUUACGAGUGGUAUUUACCCAAGAUGGCAAAGCACUUGCCAGGUGUCAACUUUCCUGGGAACCGGUGGAAUCCUGUGGAAGGAAUAUUACCUAGUGGAAUGGUCACAUUUAAUCUUUAUCAUUUUCUUGAAGUAAAUAAACAAAAAGAAACAUUUGUUUGCAUAGGAAUUCAUGAAGGCGACCCAACCUGGAAAAAGAACUAUUCACUUUGGCCAUGGGGGUCUUGUGACAAAUUAGUUCCUUUGGAGAUUGUAUUCAACCCUGAGGAAUGGAUUAAACUUACAAAAAGUAUCUAUAACUGGACCGAAGAAUAUGGAAGGUUUGAUCCAUCUUCUUGGGAAUCUGUGGCCAAUGAAGAAAUGUGGCAAGCGAGGAUGAAAACACCGUUCUUCAUCUUUAACCUGGCAGAAACUGCUCACAUGCCUUCAAAAGUGAAAGCUCAACUCUACGCUCAAGCAUAUGACCUUUAUAAGGAGAUUGUCUAUUUACAAAAGGAGCACCCAGUGAAUUGGCACAAGAACUAUGCCAUCGCCUGUGAGCGGAUGCUGCGUCUUCAGGCAAGAGAUGCAGAUCCUGAAGUGCUGUUAUCGGAAACCAUCAGACAUUUCCGUCUGUACUCUCAGAAAGCACCGAAUGACCCACAGCAAGCUGAUAUUUUAGGUGCUCUAAAGCACCUAAGAAAAGAACUGCAAAGUCUGAGAAAUAGGAAAAAUGUCUGAGACAGCAAAAUAUGAAAAACCUGCUCAUCGUUCAGCUUCCAAAAUUCUGAAGUCUGGAAGUUUUUCCUUCAAGAAAAGAAACUGCAUAAAAAAUUUAAAACUAAGUCAUCUCCCAGAUAUAAGUAUCAUGGUCCAGCAGUACUGUUUAAUGGGGUAUUCAGUGACUAAGGUCUGCUAUUUAUGCAAAAUUCUGUUUAUCCCGUGUUACCAAAUUACCAUUUCAGUGAGAAGCUUUUGAAAAGUCUUCUGACUUCCAGUCUUUCACCAGAUGACUGCACUGGAUUAGAUUCUAGAAGAGAAUGAACCAUUUUCAUAUAACUAAAUAUUGGUCAUGAACUGUGUAAGGGCCAUGCUUAUUGGGAUCAGUUUUAAAGUUAAAUUCUUUUGAUAUUAAUACCAGACCAAAGACAUUUUCUGUUUCCUGGAAAAAAAAAAUGAAUCAUGUUAGGCUUUAGGUGAGAGUACAUUUUUUACAAAGUAGCUAUAGUUGUUACAUAGUCUUACACUUCAAGCUAAACACCAAAUGGGUGAUAUUUUGAAAAAAGUUUGUGUUUUACUGUCUUAGAUCGUUCUUGGAAAUCACUAAAAAAAAAAAAAGUUAAUUUGAUGUUUGCUUAUUUCAGUUGCAGAAACUGGCGAGUAAAAAAGAUUUUGCAUUUACUUAAUUAAUUUUAUAUUUAUGUUUUAUUUCUAUUUGGACUCAGAGAUCUAGACCCAAUAAUUAGUAGGCUCCUGCUGCCAAAAUGCAAAGGGGAAAAAAAGGCAGGGAUUGGGGGGGAUGGGGAAGUGGCCCAAUAAAUUCAUUUCUGUUACAAGCAUCUUUUAUACAUAUUACUAAAGAGAACAUAGUAAGAAAUGCAAAUAAUAGUUCUUUAUUUUAUUAUGACAGUUAAUUAAUAGCAACCUGUUUUAAUGAAUAAAGUCACUCAGAGUCCUUCAGCACUUCCUAAGUAGAGGCCAGAAUCUGUAGGGCUUCUUUUCCCCCCAAUUGUAUAGCUCCUAGACUCCAAGCACUAUAUAGGCCCCUGUAUAGAAAUGCUCACUAAUGAAGAGGGAGGGCUAGAAGCUUGUCUGCAUUCAAAGAUCACUGGUGAGUCAUUCAGCAAGAAAAGGCCCCUUACCAGGAAUAGUCACAGUUCCGUGGCAUUGUACUAGCAAAAGGGUCUGAUCAAAGGUCUCCUGUGGAGCUUGCAUGGUUCCCUUUCAUACUACGACCAUAAUUAAAACCACUAAUUCUCUUUUAAAAUGCUGCAGGAUGCCAUGUAGGCAUCUGUCUGGAGUGUCCUUUGUGAUGUCAUAAGCUGUUAAGGACCAGUGCCGAGGGCUUUUGAGUGAAAUGCCAGUCAUGAAGGUGCUUCAAGACAAGGGUGCCUCUAAAAGCUUGACAGGGCCUUGACUGCACAAUUCGAGCUGAAUUUGCCCCUUGUCAGCUGCCAGUAAAUAAAUCUCAAAGGGGGAAAAGCUGAAGUUUCAUUACCUGAUCCAUGGGGCUUUGUUGGUUUUGGCAUCACACAGGGGAAGCUCUUGCCCCUCCAUUCUCUGGAUUUGAAGAUGUCCAUUGGAGCCUGCAGUGCCUGGACAGGGUUCAGAGCGGAACCUUUUGAAGAGUGUCAAUAGUUGUAACAGUUCAGCUGUUAGGAAGACAAAUAAAUGGAGGAGCUCAUUAAUCCGCUUUUGGCUCUCAGUGCCUUUUGCCCUUUUAUCACAGCCUUAUUAGGCUCCUACUCAUCUUGAACCAGAAAAAAAUGAAUUGAAGUUGUUGAGUACUAAUUGGCAAAGACUUUUAAUCAUGGGCCAAGAACUUUCACUGACUUGAAAGUAACUUCUCCACAGGGAAGGACCAAAAACCUGGUUUACCUUAAAACAAAAACCUGUUGGAGUUCAGCGUGGUGUAAAAAUGUAAGGAAGCAUUGAUAAAUUGUCUAAGUUUAUCCAUUUGAAAGAAAUUGUGUAAGAUUAUGAUAUUCUCUUUUCUUUAAAAAAAAAAGUACAAUAAAAUUCAAACAUUCCUUAGGAAA